ACUUCCGGUCGGGCCCUCGGGUCUCCCCGGAGCGGCGGCGCCUCCUCCGCCUCCUCGGCCUCCUCCCGGCGGAGACCCCGGCGCCGGGUCUCCCGUCUCCCACCCGCCGGAGAUGGAGGCGAACCCAGCGGGCAGCGGCGCCGGGGGUGGCGGGAGCAGCGGCAUCGGGGGCGAGGACGGGGUGCACUUCCAGAGCUACCCCUUCGACUUCCUGGAAUUCCUCAACCACCAGCGCUUCGAGCCCAUGGAACUGUAUGGGGAACACGCCAAGGCGGUGGCGGCCCUGCCCUGCGCCCCCGGCCCCCCGCCGCAGCCCCCGCCGCAGCCCCCUCCCCCGCAGUAUGACUACCCGCCCCAGUCCACCUUCAAGCCCAAGGCGGAGGUGCCCUCCUCGUCCUCGUCCUCGUCCUCCUCCUCCUCCUCUUCGUCCUCCUCGUCGUCAUCUUCGUCCUCUUCCUCUUCCCAAGCCAAGAAGCCCGAUCCGCCCCUGCCGCCCGCCUUCGGGGCGCCCCCUCCUCCCCUCUUUGACGCUGCUUUCCCCACUCCGCAGUGGGGCAUCGUGGACCUCUCGGGGCACCAGCACUUGUUUGGGAACCUGAAGCGAGGAGGGCCCGCGUCCGGGCCGGGGGUGACGCCUGGGCUGGGCGCUCCCGCGGGGGCCCCAGGGCCGCUUCCUGCCCCCUCGCAGACCCCGCCAGGACCCCCCGCGGCGGCGGCCUGCGACCCCACCAAGGACGACAAGGGCUACUUCCGGAGACUGAAGUACCUGAUGGAGCGGCGCUUCCCCUGCGGCGUGUGCCAGAAGUCCUUCAAGCAGUCCUCGCACCUGGUCCAGCACAUGCUGGUGCACUCGGGGGAGAGGCCCUACGAAUGCGGCGUCUGCGGCCGCACCUACAACCACGUGUCCAGCCUCAUCCGCCACCGCCGCUGCCACAAGGACGUGCCACCGGCCGCGGGGGGCCCGCCCCAGCCCGGCCCCCACCUCCCGCCGCUGGGCCUCCCAGCACCCGCUGCCAGCGCCGCCACCGCCGCCGCCCCCUCCACGGUGUCCUCGGGCCCUCCAGCCACGCCCGUGGCGCCUGCCCCCUCCGCAGACGGGAGCGCCGCCCCUGCUGGUGUUGGGGUGCCCCCUCCUGCCACCGGGGGUGGCGAUGGCCCGUUCGCCUGCCCACUCUGCUGGAAGGUUUUCAAGAAGCCCAGUCACCUCCACCAGCACCAGAUCAUCCACACGGGCGAGAAGCCCUUCUCCUGCUCCGUGUGCAGCAAAAGCUUCAACCGCAGGGAGAGUCUGAAGCGCCACGUGAAGACGCACUCGGCCGACCUCCUGCGCCUGCCCUGCGGCAUCUGCGGGAAGGCCUUCCGCGACGCCUCCUACCUCCUCAAGCACCAGGCGGCCCACGCGGGGGCGGGCGCCGGGGGGCCUCGGCCCGUGUACCCCUGCGACCUGUGCGGCAAGUCCUACUCGGCUCCGCAGAGCCUGCUCCGCCACAAGGCCGCCCACGCCCCGCCCGCUGCCGCUGCGGAGGCGCCCAAGGACGGGGCGGCCUCGGCCCCGCAGCCCCCGCCCACCUUCCCCCCGGGCCCGUACCUCCUGCCCCCCGACCCUCCCACCACAGACAGCGAGAAGGCGGCGGCGGCCGCGGCGGCGGUGGUGUACGGCGCUGUGCCCGUCCCGCUCCUGGGCGCCCACCCGCUGCUGCUCGGCGGCGCGGGGACCAGCGGGGCGGGAGGCUCGGGCGCCAGCGUCCCAGGAAAGACGUUCUGCUGCGGCAUCUGCGGGCGCGGCUUCGGGCGCCGCGAGACCCUGAAGCGCCAUGAGCGCAUCCACACGGGCGAGAAGCCCCACCAGUGCCCCGUGUGUGGGAAGCGCUUCCGCGAAUCCUUCCACUUGAGCAAGCAUCACGUGGUGCACACGCGCGAGCGGCCCUACAAGUGCGAGCUCUGCGGCAAGGUCUUCGGCUACCCGCAGAGCCUCACCCGCCACCGCCAGGUGCACCGGCUCCAGCUGCCCUGCGCCCUGGCCGGGGCAGCCGGCCUCCCCUCCACCCAAGGCACACCGGGGGCCUGUGGGCCCGGGGCCUCGGGCACGUCUGCAGGGCCCACCGAUGGGCUGAGCUACGCCUGCUCGGACUGCGGCGAGCACUUCCCGGAUCUCUUUCACGUCAUGAGUCACAAGGAGGUCCACAUGGCAGAGAAGCCAUACGGCUGCGACGCCUGCGGCAAGACCUUCGGCUUCAUCGAGAACCUCAUGUGGCACAAGCUGGUCCACCAGGCCGCCCCCGAGCGCCUGCUCCCGCCCGCACCCGGCGGCCUGCAGCCCCCGGACGGCUCCAGCGGCACGGAUGCGGCCAGCGUGCUGGACAACGGGCUGGCGGGGGAGGUGGGGGCGGCCGUGGCGGCACUGGCAGGGGUGUCUGGGGGUGAGGACGCAGGCGGGGCGGCGGUGGCAGGUGCUGGCGGGGGUGCCAGUUCCGGCCCCGAGCGCUUCAGCUGUGCCACGUGCGGCCAGAGUUUCAAGCACUUCCUGGGCCUCGUGACUCACAAGUACGUGCACCUGGUGCGACGGACCCUGGGCUGCGGCCUCUGCGGCCAGAGCUUCGCGGGCGCCUACGACUUGCUCCUACACCGCCGCAGCCAUCGGCAGAAGCGGGGUUUCCGCUGCCCGGUGUGCGGGAAGCGCUUCUGGGAGGCGGCCCUGCUGAUGCGCCACCAGCGCUGCCACACGGAACAGCGGCCGUACCGAUGUGGCGUGUGCGGCCGAGGCUUCCUGCGCUCCUGGUACCUGCGGCAGCACCGCGUGGUGCACACUGGCGAGCGGGCCUUCAAGUGCGGCGUGUGCGCCAAGCGCUUCGCGCAGUCGUCCAGCCUGGCAGAGCACCGGCGGCUGCACGCUGUGGCCCGGCCCCAGCGCUGCAGCGCCUGUGGCAAGACCUUCCGCUACCGCUCCAACCUGCUGGAGCACCAGCGGCUGCACCUGGGCGAGCGCGCCUACCGCUGUGAGCACUGCGGCAAGGGCUUCUUCUACCUGAGCUCCGUGCUGCGCCACCAGCGCGCCCAUGAGCCGCCGCGGCCCGAGCUCCGCUGCCCCGCCUGCCUCAAGGCCUUCAAGGAUCCCGGCUACUUCCGUAAGCACCUGGCUGCCCACCAGGGCGGCCGGCCCUUCCGCUGCUCCUCCUGCGGCGAGGGCUUCGCCAACACCUACGGCCUCAAGAAACACCGCCUGGCGCACAAGGCCGAGAACCUCGGGGGGCCUGGAGCAGGGGCGGGCACCUUGGCCGGGAAGGAUGCCUGACCGAGGGGUUCCCAUCCCACUCCCAUCAAAAGCCCCCUUCUGGACUCCCACCUCCCAGGACUGAUCAGACUCUUCCCCCCUCCUCGCUGUUGCCCCAUCCUUCAGAACUUCACACGGACUGGCGACCUUCAGGGCGCACGCCCGACAGGCUCAAGACUGAAUCACUCCCAUCCUCGACCUCUCUGCCCUCCCCUCAUCCCAUCAGACACUGAACCCUAUCCUCCGUCCAACCCUCGUUUGUGACCCGCAUCAGCCCCCGCCCCAGCAGCACUCUGCCCCCAGUAAGUUUUGGCGGAGAUGGGUCUGAACCGCCCCUCCCCCUCCUUUGGAAUCUGGCUGGACAGUGGAGUAUGAGCAGAGUUGGGAGGGCACAAGGGAGUGCUGGGUGCUUUUUGGGGUGGGGGGGUGGGGGGCGGGGUGGCAGACGCGGCUUGUACAGAGCGGAGAAUAAUAAAUCUUACCAUGAGGGCC